GGAAGUAGCGUCGGCGCGGGAGCUGAGCGGAGUGGCCUUGCCACCGGAGGGGAAGGGCUGCUGGCGUUAGGCCUGGCUGGGUCGUGCGGCUGAGCGUGAGGCUAGAAAGAAAAAGCGAUCCUCCAAGAGUGAGAACGGGAGAUCUGCCGAGGAUAACAACCUCCCUUGUGGCCGAAGGGCGGGGGAUCCCCACACGAGGGCUCCGCUUCGAGAGACGGCGACAAAGGAAAGUUCGUAGCGCGUUCCGGAGGCCCGGCCACCUCUGAGAAGGGAGACGACGCUGCUGGGUCCGCUGAGCGGGGCGACCCGAGGUUAGUGGAGACGGAUGCUGUCUUUUGAAGGCCUUAGUCCCUGCCCUGGUGAAGCCGACUGCGAGGUUCCACAGGGCGUGCAGGCAGUCCGGGGAUCGUUGCGAAGGGGGGUGCGGGCUAACUUAGCUGCUGCCGUUUCUAGAUGUGCAGCUGUGUAGGCCCUGUUUACAAGUGUGCAUAAGGACAGUGUAUUAAGGGAGAACUCAAGAGAAUGGAAAGGUCUUUCGGGUAGUGGUUAAAAUAAAGAAGAGUAGGAACUAGGUUUUUAAAUUUUAAAUGAAAUUAUAUCAGACAGAACUUCUGUUGGAUCUCAGGAUGCACCAUCCAAAAAUAGGACUGUAGGAGACCAAAAUAUGCCACCCUACAAUAUACUUCUAGAGUAUAUUUUGAGCUGGUAUUCUGAUAAAAUGCAGACACAGGAGUCGCUCUGAAAAUCUGUCCUGUUGUAAAAGAAAUUGACAUCUACAGAGGAAAUAUACAUCAGUAAAGGAUCUGUAUCAGAAAGAGGGCAGCUCUGCGAUAAUUUUUGUUACCUGGGAGAUCUUAUCUGCAUACCAAGACAACUUUUAUUCACCGUAUAUUUCCUCCCCUCACCUUUCCACAACUUUGUGGCCACCAUCCCCCAGAAAGCCGCAAGCCCCCAUUUCUUGAGUAGCGUAGGAUGCUGUAUAAUAUUCAAUCAUCUGACCAUGGUGGGACUCCUCUGCGUAUGUAAUUAAGUACGGGUUUUUUUUCUUGUUAAUGUCUAUGUCAGGUUAAUUUGUAACCCAGCCAAAGAACCUAGGAGGAUGGAGGGAAGCCGUUUUUCCCUCUCCUACACCUCAGUAACCUACUGCCAGCUGAAGAAAUAGAACAUUACUAAAGCCACCUGUACAUCUUUCUCCUUUUGAAUUACCUGCCCUCCGAAGAAGUAAUGGAUUUUCUGAAUUUACUGUUAACUUUUACCAUGCAGCUUUCUAUAUCUUAAUGACAUAUUUUAAUAUAUUAAUGACAUGAAUAAAUCCCUGAAUGAGGAUAUUGUACUAUUUUGCAUGUUUUAACCGUUAAAUGAAUAAUUAUAUGUGCAUCUGGCUUUUUUCAAUCAAUAUUGCUGUGGUUCAUAUUGAUAUGUUCAUAAUAGUAACUUGCACUUAAUUAACCUUUAUUAUGUGCCAGACACCAUGCUAAGCACUUUACUUCGUUUACUGCUCACAAACCCUGUAGGAUAACUUUGAUCUUCUUUUAAGAUGAGGAAACUACGGCACAGACAGGUUGCUAUAGUACUCCAUUGUAUUAAUAUGCCAUACCUUAUCCAUUCUCCUGCUUAAUUCCUCAAACUUUGUAGAUAUUCAGCUGCUAGUUAAGAAUGUGGUAACAUUUGUGUUGCCCAUAAUUUUGCUUUGUGACGUUUCUAAUAUAUAUUUUUUUAUUUUUAUUUUGAGACAGAGUCUUGCUCUGUCGCCCAGGCUGGAGUGCAAUGGCGCGAUCUCGGCUCACUGCAACCUCUGCCUCCCGGGUUGAAGCGAUUCUCCCGCCUCAGUCUCCCAAGUAGCUGGGUUACAGGCAUGCACCACCACACCUGGCUAAUCUUUUGUAUUCUUAAUAGAGACGGGGUUUCGCCAUGUUGGCCAGGCUGGUCUCGAACUCCUGACCUCAGGUGAUCCACCCGCCUUUGCCUCCCAAACUGUUGGGAUUACAGGCGUGAGCCACCGCGCCCGGCUAGUAUUUCUUUACUAUAUUCUAUUUGGCUGUCUCACCAACAGAGACAUCACACCAUUUUGUCAGUUACAGAAGAAUGAGACAUCUGGCCGCCAGAGGUCAGCCUAACUAUAUUUCGGUUAGUUUUUUUUUUUGUUUUGUUUUGUUUUAAUGGUUAAAGCCAUGGGGGUAUUGGUUCAGUAUUUUUUGAUAUUAUAAUCUGAAAAUAUUUUUUCAAAGGUGCUAGAUUAAAUUUAAACAACAUAGUAUACUGCCUUAAAGCUUACAUUUUUCCUGACUUUUGUACUGUGAAACAGAACAAAAACAAUUAUGGGAAAGUAAGAGCCUUUUUAAAAAUUUUCUGAGUAACAUAAUAACUGAAGUAUAGCCAAUUAGUAAUCUCACAGGUGCAAUCUGGUUGAAGUGAAAAUAGUAAAAAUAUUAGAGGACAGCACAAUUAAAAGCCAACAGCUUCUCCUGUCUCAGUUAAUAAAGACUUACGGUCCACGACAAAGAAUGAAUACUCUUUUUCAGAUUGAACAAGCUUAUAUAGAAUUGGUGAUAGGAUCACAACUUCUGAGGUCCCAGCAAGAGUCCUAACAUCUAGCAGCUCUACCACCAGGACAGGCCCCCUAAAACUAAUUCCAACAAGCACCUCUGAAGGUUAAGGCUACCUUUCCAGAUAAUCCAACAGCUAAAUCACCAGUUUCCAAGGGCAUUUGCAUCACCUAUGGAAAGCAUCGGAUCCUUAUACACCAGAUGUUCUUGACAGCUCAUCCCGUCAUUCCCCCCUGCACAAAAGUUGCUAUACCAGCGGACAAGCAAGACAACUACUGAGCUUCUUUUGAUUGUCAAGUAGAUAUAAUAUCACUGCCAGCAAAACAGCACAAAAAGUGUCUCUUCACAGUAUCACUACCAGUUGGGACUAUGCUAAGUAAAUCAGCUUGCCUAGAUGAGGACCCCUUCUAUUCUUGGGUAGCCAGGAUUUGAAGGAGAUACUCUGACCUGUGCCAGUGGUAAGUGACUAAUACUUUUACACACUGAACUGGUCCUGGAAACUGAGAUGUCUUCUUUGUAAGUGAAGAAUAUACAACAUAAUCUUGAAGAACGGCACAGUGGUAUGGGCCACAAGCAUACUUUAUGUGUGUAACGGACUGAAAGACAAAUUAAUCUUGGUGAAAGGAUUUUUCAUCUCUUAUUUCUAUUUGCCAGUGUUAGUCAGUGUUCUGCUGGCUUAGAUUAUUACCUUUUUCUGGUUCCUUACUGUGUUUUAUUCUGAUGGGUCCUAGAAAUCCCUCUCCUGACCACUUGUCAGAAUCAGAAAGUGAGGAAGAAGAAAAUAUUAGUUACCUAAAUGAGAGUUCUGGGGAAGAGUGGGAUUCCUCUGAAGAAGAGGACUCUAUGGUGCCCAACUUAUCGCCUCUUGAGAGUCUUGCCUGGCAGGUUAAGUGCCUUUUAAAAUAUUCCACAACUUGGAAACCUUUAAAUCCUAAUUCCUGGUUGUAUCAUGCUAAACUGUUGGAUCCAAGCACACCAGUCCAUAUACUUCGAGAGAUAGGUCUAAGACUCUCCCAUUGUUCCCAUUGUGUCCCCAAACUGGAACCAAUUCCUGAAUGGCCCCCUCUGGCCUCUUGUGGAGUCCCACCUUUUCAAAAGCCUCUUACAAGUCCCAGCCGGCUCUCUAGAGAUCAUGCCACUCUAAAUGGAGCACUGCAAUUUGCCACCAAACAGCUAAGCCGAACAUUGAGUAGAGCCACUCCCAUACCUGAAUACCUAAAACAGAUCCCUAAUUCAUGUGUUUCUGGGUGUUGCUGUGGCUGGCUGACUAAAACAGUUAAGGAAACAACUCGUACUGAACCCAUCAACACUACUUAUUCUUACACUGACUUCCAAAAGGCAGUUAACAAACUCCUAACUGCAUCACUGUAAAGAUCUACCAUUUGCUCUGAUAUCUCUGAUGUUGCUAAUUGAGAAAGUGGUACAAAGUUAGUCAUUACACAGCCCACUAAUGCCUUCUCAGUCAAACUCUCUUAUGCCCUGGCAAGCCAAUGAGGAUACCCUUUGACAAACCCUGUGGAUAAAAUGAUAAUAUCAAGGUCAGGCAUGGUGGCUCACACCUGUAAUCCCAGCACUUUGGGAGGCUGAGGCGGGUGGAUCUGCUGAAGUCAGAAGUUUGAGACCAGCCUUGCCAACACAGUGAAACCCUGUCUCUACUAAAAAUAAAAAAAUUAGCCGGGCGCAGCAGUGCACGCCUGUAAUCCCUGCUACUCGGGAGGCUGAAACAGGAGAAUCACUUGAACCCAGGAGACGGAGGUUGCGGUGAGUUGAGAUUAUGCCACUGUACUCCAGCCUGGGUGACAGAGCGAGACUCAGUCUCAAAAAAAAAAAAGGAGAAUUAGUUAAGGGGACCAUAUUACAAAAGAUAGUUGAAUAUUCUUCACACUCACUUCUCACCCUCCCCACCCCAAUUUACUCUGCCUUUCUGAAUGGCUUUAAUGAGAUACCUGAUUAUUAAUGAAGAAAAGUAGACCACCACCCCUUUUGUUAUCCAGACUUUAGAACAGCCAUUGUUGAAAGCAAGAAGUUAGCUACCCACAAUAAUACCUUUCUGAGCAUACUCUUCUCUAACAUACAUUUCUGUGGAAGUAGUUGAAUUAAAUUGAGUAACUACACAAAGGAAAAUGGCAGGGCUAUGAAUUUCUUUCCCAGCUUUUAUAUAGAUGUGCCUACAUAUGACACUCUUUAGGGUUCCUUUUAUUUUUUCUUUUUUUUUUUUUUUGAGGUAGUUGAAUUAAACUGGGUAACUACACAAAGGAAAAUGGCAGGGAUAUGAAUUUCUUUCCCAGCUUUUAUAUAGAUGUGCCUGCAUAUGACACUCUUUAGAGUUCCUUUCACUUUUUCUUUUUUUUGGAAGGGGGCGGGGAGGCAGGAGGAGUGCAGUUUUAAGCCUAGCCUAUACUACUACAAACUUAUUAUGGUACUUAAAAUUACAGCAUGAACGUUCUAUAUCGGAGUCUCCCACCAGGCUGUCUCUGACUAAAUCAGCCUAUAAGAUCAUCCCUUGGGAUUAAACAAACACCUGUUCUGUAGGGAAUGUGUUUCCUGAAUCUUGGUACUCAGACUUUUGUCAAGAGUAAAUAACAUUUCAAAAGAUGAAUGGAAAAAUGAUUAAGAGAGCAUUUCUGCUUUCAGCAUUAACUGCUAAUGGAUUAAAAUUUUAAUCUGUAUAGCAUUUCCUGGAGUAAAAGCUCAAGUACUUUCCACAUCCAUUGCAAACUUUUCAGGAACCCUUCUAAUUUUUUUUUUUUUUUUUUUUUUGAGACGGAGUCUUGCUCUGUCGCCCAGGCUGGAGUGUAGUGGCAUGAUCUCAGCUCACUGCAAGCUCUGCCUCCCGGGUUCGUGCCAUUCUCCUGCCCUGCCUCCCGAAUAGCUGGGACUACAGGCGUCCACCACCACUCCUGGCUAUUUUUUUGUAUUUUUAGUAGAGACAGGGUUUCACCGUGUUAGCCAGGAUGGUCUUGAUCUCCUGACCUCGUGAUCCACCUGCCUCGGCCUCCCAAAGUGCUGGGAUUGAACCCUUCUAAUUUUAAAGAACCUUGUUAUUAGAAAAUCUCAGCCUAAUACAAUCUGAAGUUAAGAGUUUUAGCAGCAUUGUUUUUCUAAGUAGAUUUAGCUAUAGAUUUUCUUCUGGCCAAACAAGGAAGAGUAUAUGCCCUUGUAAAUGAGUCUUGUUUUGUUUAUUUAAAUAGUCAGUCAAAACGUAGAAAUCAGUAUACGUAAAAUAAAAUGCAUGAGACUAUUAAAUCUUUUCAUAUACUCUACAAAUAAAAUGAAAUCUGUGUGUGGUCCUGGUUGACUGGGCAUCUAAAGGGAAUCAGAAAAGAGAUUGUGAAAAGUUAUAUAUAUAUCCUCUUCCUUAUUUUAGUUUUGCUUUUUCCUAUUUUCCAUAAUUAAGUGCCGUUUACAAAGUGGCAUCAAAAAAUUGAAGCAGGCCAGGCAUGGUGGCUCAUGCCUGUAAUCCCAACAGUUUGGGAGGCUGAGGGCAGGUGGAUCACUUGAGAUCAGGAGUUCGUGACCAGCCUGGCCAACAUGGUGAAAGCCCAUCUCUACUAAAAAUAUAAAAAUUAGCCGGGCGUGGUGGCAUGUGCCUGUAAUCGCAGCUACUUGGGAGGCUAAGACAGGAGAAUUGCUUGAACCUGGGAGGUGGAGGUUGCAAUGAGCUGAGAUCGCGCCACUGCACUCCAGCCUGGGCAACAGUGAGACACCGUCUCAAAAAAAAAAAAGGUUAGGAAUCACAAAUUGUGUAAAUAUAUAGCAACUUUAAGAAGAGAGAAGAAUGCUUAUAACCUAGUGAAUAUUUCUGCUGAGCCUUAGUUGUCUUGUCUAAAGGAAAAAAGAGGGAAUUGUAGAAUAAAAGUAUUUGUUAGUGGAAAUUAUUGACCUGAAACCAUAUCAUAUUGUUAGUGUAACUGAAUGUAUCAGAAAUUGUUCCUAUGUAGGUAUUCUGUGAAACUGGUUUCUAAAAUGUUACAGGAAACUGUUUCCUUUUUUUUUGUUUGUUUGUUUAAGUGGAGGUGGGAGGAGGUAGGGAAGAGGUCUGAAUAUUAAAAUAUGUUUAUGUUCAUGUGUUCAUAAUACGUUCCUUUUUCUCUCUGUGUGUGUAUAAAAGUGCCUUGCUCAUGAAUGCAUUUUUGCUAUUCACUUCGAAAGGAAGCCUUUCCCCAGCUUGGCAGCUGAAUAAACCAAUAGCUUUGUACAUGCUGAA